UGAGCAAAUAAUUUAAACAUUUCAAUAAAAUACUGUGCUGCCCAACCAGAUAAGUUUGCAAGCUUGAUUUAUGACUCUGACGUCGAUAAAUUUGUGAAUUCAGAAGGUAGCUGGUUUGAUAGGUGCAAUAUAAAUGAUAUGUUCAUUAUAAUCUGAGAUAAUUGACUAAAAUGAUUAUGGUAAUUACAUUUCUCGUGUUGUAAAGUACCAUAAGGAUCAUCUAGUGUAUCCAUUUUAUUUUAUAGUUAAGAAAACAGGACCUUACAACGUUUAAUGACUUUCUGUGUUUGCAGUCAUAUCUAUUGAGACUUUUAGAACCAUACAAAGCAAGCUAAAGGGUAACAGUGCCAGUGCCGCCUUCUGAAAAUGCAUUUGGAUAUCUCUUGUGUCUUUUAUUUUCAGAAACAAGGUAUUGCUGUGAUGUCCAGGCUAGAGUGCGUUGGCUAUUCACAGGUGUGAUCAUAGCGCAUUAUAGGCUUGAACUCCUGGGUUCAGGCAUUCUCCUACCUCAGCUUCCCAAGUAGCUGGGACUUCAGGCAUGUGCCACCAUGCCUGGUUCUUGUGUCCUUAUUAGUAAUAACUUGGGUUUAUAUAGCACUUUUCCAUGUGCCUUCACAUAUAGGUGUUAUUCUCAUUUGGUCACAGAAGAAACUGAGUCCUAAAGAAGUUUUGUAACUUGCUUAAGUUCACACAGCUCAUUUAUGAGAGAUAGUGUGUUCAUUAUAAUUUAUCCUACAUCCUGGUACAUCUUUGAGUAUGAUAAUUACACUGGGACAAUAGGCACAAAUCGGGGGUCCUGGGAAGUCUCAGAUAGAGGGUCCCCCUAGUGAUGGAACUGAUGUUAGGAUCUAGUACCUUUAUUUGUAAACUUUCCCUGUCUUAGCAGGAAGAUAAAUAAUAUGACAAAAUUAAGGUUUCUCAAGGGAAAAAUGUAUGUGUGUAGAAUAGAGAAGCAUAAAAAAGUAUCAUAUGGAAAAAGUAGACAGAAGUCAUUUUCUUCUUUAUGGUAUUUAUUUAUUAAGGAGAAGUUGAUGCUUGAGACACAAAGCCUAUUUUAUUUUAUUUUAGUUUAGUUUAGUUUAGUUUAGUUUAGUUUAGAGACAGUGUCUCACUCUGUCACCCAGGCUGGAGUGCAGUGGCACAAUCAUAGCUCAUUAUAACCUUGAACUCCUGGGCUCAAGUGAGCCUCCUGCCUCAGCCUCCUGAGUAGCCAAGGUUACAGAUGUGUACCACCAUGCCUAGCUAUUUCUUUUUUCAAAGUUUUUGGAGAGAUGGGGUCUCACUAUGUUGCCCAGGCUGGUCUUGAACUCCUGGCCUCAAGUGAUUCUCCUCCCUGGCCUCCCAAAGUGCUGAGAUUUCAGGCAUGAGCCGCCUUUCCCAGCCAGAGCCUAUUUUAUAACAAAGCUGUGAACAUCUCAUGUAAUUUAGUGAAUACUGCACUGAAAGUAAAAAACAGGAUGGUUAUAUGGGCAUUCACAAUUAACAUACACAACUGAAAACACCCUGGACCUGGGAUGUUUGAAGCAUUGAACUAAAAUUAAUUGUGGAUGCUGGGGAUGCUACAGCGACCAGGUUAUCAAUUUCUCUGUCUCCUGAUGAGGCUCGAGAGUAGCUGGUAGGGGACCCUGGAGUAUCUAUACUUGUUGAUGGUUUAGUGGGCGUAGUGCUCUUCAAGAAGUUAGUAAGUAUUGGUUUUUUACCCUUGCGAUUGUGUGGCUGACUAGGAUCUGUGGCUUACCGCACUACCCAGCAUUGCAAGAGUAUCACAUUGUAUAUUGCUAGGCCAGGAAAAGAUCAGAGUUCAGAAUCUAAAGUACGGUUUCAACUGAAUGCAUGUUGCUUUCACACCAUUGUAAAGCUGAAAAAUUGUAAGUCAAACCAUGGUUAAGUCCAGAUGCUUCUGGAUUUAUUAUGGGGUUAUGUCCUGAUAAACCCAUGGUAAAAUUGAAAAAUCAUAAGUAAGCUCACCUAUCAUAAGUAAGGGGCUGUCUGUAUUUCCUAGUUUUUGGCUUAGUGCUUUGUUAGGCUUUUUAUUUUCCCCCAUGUAUUUUACUCACACUUCAGGUCUCCAUUUUGUAGUAGAUAGGAGUGGGCGAAACUAAGUACUGUUUGAGUUUUUAAGUUGGCUGCAUUGUCUGAGAUGCUUUUAGGAUGUAAGAUUUCAUAUAAUGGGAAUACAGAAGUAACUAUCAUAACAUAGAGGAUUUUAAUUUAGAUAUAUAUUUGAGUGUCCUAAUGACUUUUUUCCCAAAUUUUUAAAAAGAAACAGACACACAACUUCAUGUUAUGAGGUUUUAAUGGAUCCUUGAAAAAAUUUGGAAAUGAAAAGGUAAUAAAGAGAGAACAAAUGUAGCAAAACAUGCAAACCCUUCAAUUAGAACAAUUCAAUGUUUCUAGGAAAUAUGUUUGAAAUAUUAUAUUUAUUAAUUACUUUAUUUUUAGAUAUGUGUAAGGUUAAAGUAAAAUGAAAGAUUUACUGGAUAACUGUGCUUAAAAUAUUUACUGGAUAACAUGAUUAAAAUAUUUUCUUUCAAGCUUUAAGAUAAAAUAUUCCAUUUCUUAAUUUCCAAAAUGUGAGAAGACUUUAUUUAGGGCUUUCAGUUUAAUUCCCAUUAGGGAGGAAUGAAAUUAAUCUAGAAACAGAUUUAUUAAGACAUCCUACUACUGAAAUUUUUAUUGUAGAAGAUAAAGAAGACUAUGACUUUUGCCAAAGAACAUAAUUAUUUCCAGGAUUUCUUUGUGAUAAUGGCCCAUAUCAGCGUUAGAUAAUUAAUUCUGGUUGAAUAUAUGGAAUCAGAGAAAUAUCUAAUUCCUGCGCUUUCCAUCAUCUACUUUCCCUAGGGCAAUAGGCUCUAUAGGCAUGUGAUUCCGCCUGCCUUCAAGGGAGUCUCAGGUGACAGGUUUGGCAGGCAUUUUACUGUGACAAACAAGGGUCACCAGUUUAUGACCUUUUUCAGUUAGCAACAUCUGCUUUCUUGUUUUGAGGGACCCAACUGCCAAACCAACGCUUCAUAUUUUAUAUUUAUGUAACAUCAGCACACCACUUCUGGCACCAGUUUCUAUGAUUGUUUGGAUAUGAGCUAAGCUGCUAUAAUAGGCACUUCUCCAAAGCACAGUGGCCCAGUAAAGACAGAAGCUUAUUUUUGUCUUAACAUUCUUUCUGUUAUUUCUCUCUUAUUUCUACUUAAGGGAAACAGGUGGGUCAGGAUGGACAGCACUGCCCAUUUCUUGUAUUUUGUUGCUCUGCCAUCCCUUGUCAUCUGUGCGGUCAGAGAUGCCUCAUCCACAUUUGUACCCCAGUCUGUGAGAACAGAGGGAAGCACAAGAUGUGGAAAUGGCAUGUUACUUCCACUAACAUUUCAUCAGUGAGAAUUUAAUCUUAUGACUAUGCCUGCACUCAGUCAGGGGCAGGCAGGUGUUUUCUCUCCAUGGAUGGUCAUGUACCCAGCUAAAAUGCUGUUACUAGGAAAGAAGGAGAGAUUAGAUUUUGGGGAAUGCCUAGCAAUCUGCCAGAGUUACUUAAUUCCUCGGAAUCUUAGCUUCCUCUUCUCUAAAAUGUGGUAAUAAUUUUAUCUACCUCAGAGAGUUGUCUCGAAAAUUGGGUAAUACAUAGAAAGUAUAGUUUCUGAGGCUGAGGAAGGCAGAUCACUUUGAGGCCAGGAGUUUGAGACCAGCCUGGCCAACAUGCUGAAACCGCAUCUCUACCAAAAAUACAAAAAAAAAAAAAAAAAAAAAAAAAUUAGCUGGGUGUGGUGGCUGGCACCUGUAGUCCUGGCUACUCAGGAGGCUGAGGCAGGAGAAUCACUUGACCCUGGGGAGGCAGAGGUUGCAGUGAGCCAAGAUCGUGCCACUGCACUCCAGCCUGGGCAGCAAGAACGAGAUUCCAUUUCAAAAAAAAAAAAAAGAAAAAGAAAAGUAUAGUUUCUGGUAUAUAUAAUAUGCUCAAUAAAUGUUAGUUUUUAAUUAUGAAGAUAUUUUUCUAACGACAAGAGUAGCUAUUGCUUUUUAGUUUAUUAAUGCAUAAAGAACUUGUAAGCAAUGCUUAUUUUACUUCAGAAAAAUUCUACUAUUUAAAGCAGUAAAAGGCGCAGACCUAAAUACGUGGAGACCGUAGAUAUUACAGCACCAUAACAUCUGGGUUCUUUUUUUUUUUUUUUGCUUAUUUUUGAAAAAGCAAAAUUAUUAAUGGAACAACCAUUUACACUGUUUCUUAGAAUGGUUUUAAUGUAGAUAAAGCAUAAGUAGGUUUUGAGGUAAGUAGUCCAUUAGAGUAAUUUAAUUUCCCUUGCAAAAAUUUUAGUUAGUUUUUUUUUUCCUUCUAAAAUGGGUCAUCGCUAAAAGCAAUUCAUUUAUUUGGCAAGAUAUUCUUAGCAUAUGGAUUUGAUGCGGCGGUGAGAAUUCUAAAAUGCCUAUGUAAUUUAAAAAGUUGUUUCCUGGUAAUUGGCUGAGGGAAACAAACGAUAAAGUUUUUACUAGCCUAAAGAAAAACAAAAGCUGAAACAUAUACAAAAGUGGAAAUAAUUUACUAAUAUUUUAAACUGCUUGAGUUUGAAAGUAGGGAAAGUAACCUAGUAUUAUGACUAUUCGCAUGUACUAUACAUUAUUUGUCAUUGAUAGCUAUAAUGAAACAUUUAAAUCCACAAACAAUUAUUCUUUAUUAUUUUAUAGACAAUUAUUAUUUUUGAAUAAAGAAAGAUAACUUUAUUUUGGGUUUUGGUUUCUUUACUUGUUAAUUUCAGCCAGUUAAUUGUUAAGGUUCAUUAUAAUUUUUGAAAGCACUUUUUAGCAGAACUCAGUUUUUGGUCAAGAAGCAAAGAUGAAAAGUGACUAGGAAGUUAUUCAGAGAUUUUUCACUAGUUUUGUGAAAUUGGUGGUUAAUGUGGUUAAAGCAGUCUGUAUCCACUAGAAAUAUGUCUUAAAGAUGAGGAAGCUGAACUUUAAAUCUAUUUGUUCAUCUAUUCCCCACUUUCAAAGGACAUAUGGGAAAACAAAGUAAAGAACAUGUCAAGUUAAAUUUUUUUUUAAACUUAGCAUCUCUAAAGCAUGUUCAUUUGUUGCAUAAGAAUUCUUCUUUGGUUUCCUAUUUUUUGGGCAAAAUGCCGAAAGAGGAUAUGUGUGCCAUCUGCUUUGUCAUCAUCAAUUUUAGAUUAAAUUCCCCAAAUUUAGAUUGAGUUUUCACUGAUUUAACCUGCAGCUUUUGGUAAUUUUUUUCCUUGAUCUCUGGCAUAGCUUCUGACUAUUUUGUGGGUGAGUUAAAGAUGAUGUUUAGAUGUAGUAAGAUAGGGGUUGGGUUACUGCAGCCACUGGCCUUGCAAUUAGUUAAGUUGGACUUCAUUGUGAAGUUAGUGGGGAGCAUUGGGCAAAAGAGAGUGGUGAAUUUUACCAAAAGGUUUUUCUGUUUAAUUAAUUCAUUAUUAGCUAGGCUCCGUUUAACUAUCUCUGUGAAGAAAUAGUUAAAUUGCUUGCCUCAAAAAAAAAAAAAAAUCAAAGCAUAGAAACAAAUUACCACUCAACUUUUAAUGUAUUGUCUACUAGACUGUACUGCUCAUUAGGCUUUUAUUUGAUAUGCUAUUUUAUUUUUCAAUUUUAAAUUAUAAUCUAUGUAAAUUUGGAAUAUUGAAUGUAUAGGAUGGAGAUGACUUUAAUUGCUGUCAAACUCCAAGGAUAAGUUAAGUAGGAGGCAUGAGGUUGAGGAACAUAAGUUUUUAUGAGAAAAAAUAAGGUUAAGAGGGAAUAAGAAAAAACAGUAGUGAAUGUUUAAAUUAAAAAUAUUUCCUCUUUCCCUCAAUUUUUAAUUUAAAAAAACUUCUAACUGCAAAAAAAGUUGAAAUAAAAAGAAAAAGCAGCACUCAUAAGAUCCAUCUGUUGCAUUCUGUCACAUUUGAUUCUCUAUGUAUGUGAUAUAUUUAUUUAGAAAGCUUUUAAAAAUAAGUUAUAGAUACCAUUAAACAUCCUGCCUGAAUACUUCCACACUUCCUGAGAAUAAGGACAUUAUCCUACCAUCCCUAAUAUUAUUGUUUUUGUGGUUAUUACUGUUGCUGAAUCUUCCUAAUUAAUCAUAAUUCAAUAAUAUCAUCUCAUGUACAUUUUAUGUUGAAUUAUCCCAUUUUUUAAGGAUCCAGGAUGCAAUAAAAUUUCACACAUUGCAUUUGAUUGUCAUGCCUCUUAAUCUCAUUUUAAUCUGGAAAAAUUCCCCUGCCUUUUUUUAAAAUUAUGACUAAUUUGAAGAGUGUAGACCAGUUAUAGGAUGUUCUAUAUUCUGGAUUUGUCUGUUUCCCAUUUUUUAGAUUCACUUUUUUUGGCAAGAAGACAGCUGAGGUGAUAUCACUACUACUUCCCAUCAGAAGGCACAGGAUGUCUGCUACUGGUGAUUGUGGAAUGGGAUUGUUUGGUUAAGUGUUAACUACUGUAGCUUUCCCAUAUACAAGUACCUGUGUCCUUUUGUGAUUAGUAAAUAGUCUCUGGGAUGAUACUGUGUGAGAUCAUGUGAAUAUCCUAUUCCCCAAUAAUAUUUUCCCAGGUACUUCUAGGCAUUCAUAGGUGAUUCUUGCCUGAAUUAAUUACAGUGAAGAUUGCAAAGGGAUUAUGUUCUAAUUCUGUAAUCCCUUUUUCAUUUAAUAGAUAGCAUUUUGCAAGAACUUCCCUCACAUCCUUCCACUCCCCCUUAAUAUGGAUUCAUGGAUUUUUAAGUUAAAUGUAUUAUAUUUAAUACUUGAUGAUCAGUAUUAUAUUUUUAGAUGCACAAAUUAUUCAGAUCUAGCUAGUGGGUGCCUUUUCAAGCUGGUUCCUGUGUUCUUUACUUGACUCCUGUAGUCUUUGAGCACUUUCUUGCAUUCAGGAAUGAAUUUUGUUUGUUUGUUUUUGUUUUUUGAGAUAGAGUCUCACUCUGUCACCCAAGUUUGAGUGCAGUGGUGGUGUGAUCUCGGCUCACUACAACCUCCGCCUCCUGGGUUCAAGCGAUUCUCCUGCCUCAGCCUCCUGGGUAACUGGGAUUACAGGUGUCCGCCACCACAUCUGGCUAAUUUUUCAAUUUUUAGUAGAGGCGGGGUUUUGCCAUUUUGGCCAGGCUGGUCUCAAACUCCUGACCUCAAGUGAUCCACCUGCCUCGGCCUCCCAAAGUGCUGGGAUUACAAGCGUGAGCCACCGUGCCCAGCCAGGAAUGAAUAUUUUUUACGUGACUAAGAUAACGUUAUAACAUUUAUUUUAUAAUAAAACAGUAAAAGUGGUUUAGACAUUUUACACAAACUAAUUUUCUUCUAUCAUCAAUUGUUUGAUGGAAAGUUCUUCUUAUAGUUUCAGUGAUAACUGAAAUAAGUGUAUACCUCUUAAUUAUUGAAGAUUAUAAGCAUAUCAAGAGGCUGGUUUCUGGUGUGUUUCUCAAAGCUAGUACUUUUCUCUAAUUUUUGAGACAGGGUCUCUCCCAGGCUGGAGUACAUUGUGCGUUCAUGGCUCACUGCAGCCUCAACCUCCCAGGCUCAAGCUAUCCUUCCACCUUGGCCUCCAAGCAGCUGGGACUACAGGUGUGCCUCACCACACCUGGCUAAUUUUUUAAUUUUUUGUAGAGACAGGGUCUUGCUAUAUUGCUGAGGCUAGUCUUGAACUCCUGGGCUCAAGUGAUCCUUCUGCCUCAGCCUACCAAAGUGCUGGGAUUACAGAUGUGAGCCACCAACCCUGGCCAAAGCUGGUACUUUUCUGAUUUGUGAUUCGAAUAAAAAAUUCUGAGUGCUGCCUCCUGGGAACCUCUGUGAAUGGAUGCCUAAGAUGGAGAAAUACUUUGGGACAGCCCGCCUUACAUGUAUUUCUGCUCUGUCCCUCCUGCUUCUUGUAUAUUUUGGAAAUGCAGUGAUAAGGCUGGGGUUUACUUGUGCUCAUUUUCCAUUAUCUUUCCCACAUUUUAAUUGGACAAUAUCUAAAUUGCUUCUCUGUAUCCACUUUACCUGUCUUUUAUAUUUCCAAGCCCUCUUUCAGCUUUAGCUACUGAAAAUGCCAUUGAAAACAGUUUAAAUAAAUAACUCAUACAGGGAGAAUAUCAUUAAAUUUUAAAUAUUGUCAAAAGAAUGUGCUGUAAAGUAUACUGAAUUCCUCCUUUGUAAAAUUCUGGUAUAAGUGGUUUUACUUCUUUAUACAUUUAAAGUACAUGUAAGAAAUUUAGUAUGUAUCACUUGUGCUAUUGUUUCUAACUUGGUUGGAGGGUGGGAGGGUUUAAAGCUGGGAAAGGGAAGGAACUAUGAAGGAGUCUUUUACUAGACUGACAUUUAUUCCACCAAUUCAUUGUCUUUGGAUAUUCUGCUUAACCACCUGCAAAUCUAUUCAGCGUAUCAUUAUUUAGGCUGCAUGUCUCUAUUCUUGGCUACAAGAGUGUUUUAAGAGACUUCAUACCAUGCCGACAUCUAAAUAUGCUGUCUAAAGCGUUGUCAUACCCACCAUUCUCCUAACCAUGUCAAAAGGAAAUAACGUGUUUGGCAUAACUUAUUCUUAGUGAAACCCUGCUGUUUUCUACUGAUUGCCUCUUUUCAUUGCCUCUAAGUUCUCACAGACCACUUAUUUGGUAAACUAUUUUAGAGGUGUGCAGGGUAGGACAUCAGGCUCUGUGAGUCUCAGAAUCUACCUUUCCUCCUAAUCUUUGCCCAUCCCAAGACAUCAGUUCUUUCCCUGUAGCUGGAUGUUGCCUGUGCUGCUGGGUAAGGCAAAUCUCUAACUAAGAAGUCAUUGUAUGUAUUAGGGGAACCAGCCCCUGAUAUUUCAACAUAGGUUCUUUUCUAUUUUCCCUAAGUGCCGGCCGGUCUGAGAAAUAAAGGGAAAGAGUACAAAAGAGAAAAAUUUUAAAGCUAGGUGGCCGGGGGAGACAUCACAUGUCAGCAGGUUCCAUGAUGCCUCCUGAGCCGUAAAAAACAGCAAGUUUUUAUUAGCAAUUUUCAAAGAGGAGGGAGUGUACGAAUAGGGUGUGGGUCACAAAGAUCACAUGCUUCAAGGGCAACAAAAGAUCACAAGGCAGAAGGUCAGGGCGGGAUCACAAGGUCAGGGCAAAACUAGAAUUACUAAUGAAGUUCCAUGUCCCACUGUGCACGCAUUGUCAUUGAUAAACAUCUUAACAGGGUUCAAGAGCAGAGAGCACAUCUGACUAGAAUUUGCCAGGCUGGAAUUUCCUAAUCCUAGCAAGCCUGGCGGCACUGCAGGAGGCCAGGGCGUGUUUUAUCCCUUAUCUGCAGCUGCAUAAGGCAGACACCCCCAGAGUGGCCAUUUUAGAGGCCUCCUCUGGGAAUGCAUUCUUUUCCCAAGGCUGUUAAUUAUUAAUAUUCCUUACUGGGGAAAGAAUUCAGCGAUAUUUCUCUUACCCGUUUUUGGUAAUAAGAGAAAUGUGGCUCUGUCCUGCCUGGCUCCCAGGCAGUCAGACCUAAUGGUUAUCUCCCUUGUUCCCUGAACAUCGCUGUUAUCCUAUUCUUUUUUCAAGGUGCCCAGGUUUCAUAUUGUUCAAACACACAUGCUUUACAAACAAUUUGGGCAGUUAAUGCAAUCAUCACAGGGUCCUGAGGCGACAUACAUCCUCAGCUUACGAAGAUGACAGGAUUAAGAGAUUAAAGUAAAGACAAGCAUAGGAAAUUAUAAGAGUAUUGAUUGGGGAAGUGAUAAAUGUCCAUGAAAUCUUCACAAUUUAUGUUCUUCUGUCACGGCUUCAGCAAGUCUCUCCGUUCGCGGUCCCUGACUUCCCGCAACAGUAUGGACUUUUUUGUGGGAAAAUUAUUUGUGUGGAUCUACCAAGGAAAUGUCUGCAGAGUCCACUUUGAGAAAAGCUGACUUGAGAAACUGAUUUUCUGGACACAUUGUAUCAAUUAUUUCUGUAAAUGAGAAGUCACUGAACUGGUAAAAUAUAUAUCUUUUAGAUUAUCCAAAAAAAUGAACAUGCAAUUAAGAUUUUUUUUAAAGCUCAGUUCCCUGGGACAGGGACAGGGAGUGCGGGCAUAUGAAGAUCUCAGAUAAGAAACAGUGGUUAAGGCUGGGCACAGUGGCUCAGGCCCGUAAUCCCAGCACUUUGGGAGGCCCGAGGUGGGCAGAUCACCUGAGGUCAGGAGUUUGAGACCAGCCUGGCUAACAUGGUGAAACCCCGUCUCUACUAAAAAUACAAAAAUUAGCUGGGCAUGGUGAUGGGUACCUGUAAUCCCAGCUACUUGGGAGGCUGAGGCAGGAGAAUCACUUGAACCUGGGAGGUGGAGGUUGCAGUGAGCCGAGAUCGCGCCAUUGCACUCCAACCUGGGCAACAAGAGUGAGACCUUUGCUGUUAAAGGGUGGUCCCUGCAGCAGCAACAUCAUCAGGGUGCUUCAUAGAAAUACAGACUCUCAGGCCCUAAUCCAGCCCUGUUGAAUCAAAAUCUGCAUUUUGACACCAUCUCCAGGUGAUUCAUAUACAAAUUAGGUUUGAGAAGCUCUGGAAAUCAUUUUCAUGGGACCGUCCCUCUCUGCAAGUGAACUGGUAGAGAGAUAAAGACUCAUCUUGUGAAGUACCUGCAGAUACUAAAUAGCAUAAUUAGGAAAAUCCUUUUAGAGUGAAAGGAAUUCAGAUAUUUAUUGUACAUUGUUGGCUCAAUACAAUUGUUUAAUAUUGACCUUCCCACACUGUACCUUGUGAGAUUUAAGAUGUAUGCAAAUACAAUGACUAUUAUUUUCAAAAAAUGAUUUUUGUAGUCAUUUUACUAGCCAUAAGCCAGAGUGCUCAAAACCUUUCCCCCUUUUUCUGCUUUCUGUAUUCUUUCUAAAGGUGGCUAAAUUGUCGAAGUUAUAAUUCAGCAUGAAGAGAAAACUCCAAGAAAAAAGGCUUUAGCUGGGGCCAUGCCUCUGUUGUUUGCAUCCUAACUUUGUUAGAGCUCCUUAAGCACAGUAGAGCCUCGUCUGUUCCAUGACACUGCAGGCUUGUCGCAUAACCCUAUGAGCAGUAAUCAACUGGACUCCAGAUGUUGCUGUCUCACAUUAGCCCAACGUUAGCUUCAAUAAUGUUGAUGGCAGCUUGAUAUAUAUCAGGGUUUCCUAGCUUUCUUAGAUGUCUUACUUAUAUUGGGGGUGAUGAAGGAAUUGAACCUCCUCCCUUUAGCUGAGACAUCCCCACGUGUUUCUGAAGGGUGGACAUGUCAGGUAGGACUCUGAUGGGCUGGUGUAUGUGCUGUUGAAGAAAAUACUUUAAGCCAAUGUCAGAUUGCAGGUGCAUCUUACUGGCUCACUCAGGUGGGAGGGUCUAAUGGGAACUGUGGGUGUUGUGAGCUGGCAGAGGGCAUCAGUAUGGUGUAGUGAAAAGAACAUUGUGUUUCUAAUUAGGUAGAUGUGGUUUGAAUCCCAGCUCUCCUGCUUAUUAGUUCUGCAACCUAGUAGCAGUUAUUUAGUCUCUGAUUUUUGAGUUCCAUAAUUGUAAAAAUAGGGUUAAUUUCUAUCUCCCUGGGUUGUUGUGAGACUCUAAUGAGAUGAUGUAUUAAGAGCCUAAUAUAGUGCCUGGCAUAGAGUAGGUGCCCAUUGAAUGGUAAGUUCACAUUACUAAUCCAUUUGGUAUAUUAAACAAUUCCAUACAGGUUUUUUUAAAUGCCUGCCCCAGCUAAACUAAGUAAGGAUUUAAGUAGCUUCUGAUAGUUUUGCCCAUCAAAUGUAUUUUCAAGUGAUUCUUUGCCAGGUAAGCAUCAUCUUCUGUUAUUGCUGCUGUGGCAGACACAGGCCUUCAAAGGCACAAUGCUGUCAACCUGGCAGAUUCAUCAGCUGGAUCAGAGCCAGCAGGGAUUACAUGUCCAGAAAGCUGAGAAUAUUCCAUUUUACACAAGGGAUACGCCAACAUGUCAGCUAGAAUCAAGGAAAAGGGACUACGUGCUUAAAACAAUAGCAAGUGGUAAAAAGAGCUUUGGUGAAUUAAUCACGUUCAAAUGGUUGCAGUACCUGGUGUUGUUUUCUAUGAAGAAGGCUAUGAAAUGCAACAUUUUGUUUCAAAAAGUAUGCUCAUGCUCAUAUAGUAUCCUGGAAAGGACAUUUUUCUUUAUAAUUAUAAAGGGUGUAGAGUUUGAUGUAAAGCUCUCCAAAUUCACAACUCUGCUUAUAUCAGGAAACCAGGAGGUGUGGCACAAAAUCCUAACUUAUUAGUGUUCUACCUGUGAAUAUUUGACUGUAGACUUCUUCCAUUACUUUUCUCUCUCUAUCUCUGAAUCUGAACCCAUAGCCCAUCUGAGUUUGAAAGCUCUGAUUUUAGGUAUUGAAGUAGUGCCUUGGUUAUUUUUUAACUUUUAAGUGGUUGCUGUUUAGAAAAUGUUAGAAAAAUAACUUUAAUCAGAUUUAAGAAAACUACUGGAUGAAGAAUAUUUUUUGUUUUGACUAAAUUACAUUGAUUCAUCUUUUAAAUGGGGAUUAUAAUGGUACCUAUUCCAUAGGAUUAGUAUCUACCUUACAGAAUAAAUAAAGUAUUAAUAAUAUAUGUGAAGUGUUUAGUAUAUGGUGCUUGGCAUGCCAUAAACAUAUUUUAUAAUCGUGUUAAGUAUUAUUAAUUUUUUGCUAUUGGUUUCUCUCUGCUUACAAAACAGAAAUUUUCAUUGUAGAAAAUGUAAAAUAAAACAAAGAAAAAAAAUCACAUAAAUGCUCUAAUAACAGAUACUGACAUUUUAGUACAUCUUCCCAGCCUUCUGUUUCCCUACAUGCAUAUAUUUUACAUAAGCAAAUCAAAAUUGUAGUAGUUUUAAACUUGCAUUUUUCACUCAUUAUAUUAGCAGUAUUUUCCCAUGAAAUAUUAUCACAUGAUUUUAAUGUCAUUUUAUUUUACUUAUGCCCUAAAACUUGUUUCCUCUAUUGUUAGAUAUUUGUGUUUUCAGUCUUUCAUUAGUUAUUAGGAGCUCUCCAGUGAAUUUUUUUUUCCCCUUGGGCUGAGUUGGAAGAGGAAUUACUGGAUUAAAAGCUGUAUACACUUUUGUGCACAUUGCAAAACUGUCUUUCAGGGAAGUUCUACAAAUUUAUACUCAUACUUGGAAUAUAUGAAAUUUGGUGCUUACUCCUUCUGACACUGGGACAUGAUACUUUUUUUUUUUUUUGAGGUGGAGUUUUGCUCUUGUUGCCCAGGCUGGAGUGCAAUGGUGCAAUCUUGGCUCACUGCAGCCUCCGCCCCCCAGGUUCAAGCAAUUCUCCUGCCUCAACCUCCCAAGUAGCUGGGAUUACAGGAAUGUGCCACCACGCCCUGCUAAUUUUGUAUGUUUAGUAGAGAUGGGGUUUCACCAUGUUGGUCAGGCUGGUCUCGAACUCCUGACCUCAGGUGAUCCGCCCACCUCGGGCUCCCAAAGUGCUGGGAUUACAGACAUGAGUCACUGCACCCUGCCAGACAUAAUUUUUAAAAAGUCUCAAUUUAAUGGGUUAAAAAAUACCAUUUUUAUGUAAAACUUAAAUAUUUUCUACUAGUAUUGAACUUUUUAUGUUCAGAAACUCUAUUAUUCUAUAUGAGUUUGCUUAUCUGUGUCCUUUGAACAUUUUGUGGGAGUUAGUUAUUUAUAGAAAUCUCUAAUUUUUAAGGCUAUCAACUCUUAAUCAGGAAUACUGCAAGUAUUUUUCCAUAGUUUUCAAUUUGCCUUUUAAGUUUGUUCACAAUAUUUUUGAUAGAGAUUUUUAGUUUUUGGUAGUCAGAUGUAACAGUUUCUUUUUCUUCUUUGUUUCUGCCUCUGUGUUAUGCUUGGGAUAUCUAUCUCCACUCCAAGAUUACACCAUCGUCUAUGUUUUAGUUCAUUUCUUCAUCCACGUACUUUAAUCCCACAGAUGUUCAUUGAAUGUCUCUUAUAUGGCAGGGCUAAGACAAUUGCCAGGCAAAAAGUAAUAUACCUUACACAUUUGGAGCUUCAGUCUGGUAGGAAAUUGACCUUAAUAAGGACAUGAUGCUAAGUGAAAUAUGCCAGGCACAGAAAGAUAAAUACUGCAUAAUCUCACUUAUAAAUGGAAGCUAAAGAAAGUCAACUCAUAGAAACAGAGAGUAGAAGGGUCGGGAACGGGAGAAAAUGGGAGAUAUUGGUCAAAGGGUACACACUUCUAGUUAUAAGAUGAAUACAUUCUGGAGACUUACUGUACAGCAUGAUGACUAUAGUGAAUAAUAAUAUAUUGUAUACUUGAAAUUUGCUACGAGAAUAGAUCUUACAUAUUCUCGCCACAAAAUCAAGGUAAUUAUGUGAGGUGAUGGACAUGUUAAUUGGCUUGAUUUUGGUAAUCAUUUCAUAAUGCAUACAUAUAUCAAAACAUCAUGUACUCUUUAAAUAUACAGAAUUUUCAUUUGUCAAUUAUACCUCAGUGAAGCUGCAAGAAGAAGAAAAUAGGCCUUAAUUUCUCUUAAAUUUGCACAAAUAAAAUUAAAACUGUGCUAAGUAUUAUGAAGGAGAGGUAAAUAGUAAAAUAAAAAUGUCUACUGAGGUUAACUGACCUGCUUGGGGAGGUCUGGGAGGGAUUUCCAGUGGAAGUGGCCUUGAUGGAAGAUUGUAGUUGAAUCACAUAAGGACGUGGUGGAGGAAGGCAUUUCAGGCCUGGCAGAUGCCACUGUGGCUGAAGCACAGAGAUCAAGAAAGAUAAAGCAGGAUUAUGUCAAGAAAUGGCUGGAAAGGAGUUUUGAAGCUAGACCUUGUGGGGACUUGUAAGUCUUGUUAAGGAUUUUGAUACUUUGUUGUAAGAGCAAUGGAAAACCACUAAUGCCAUUUAAGGAGGAUGCUCAGAGUAGGUGAUAUGAUGCUGUCUUUUCUUUUUAAAAAAUACUUAACUCUUUAAUUCUUUUGGAGUUUGUUUUUAUGGGGCCUACAAAUUUUUUUUCUAAGCAGUUAAAGUCACUGUACCUUUAGCUGAAUAAUUUUUUCUUUUCCCAUUUUUCUGAAGUGUACUCUUAUCAUAAAGUAAAAUUUUAUAUAUCACUUGUGUCUUUUAUGCAGCAAGAUGUUUUGAUAGGACCUAUGUGCUAUGAUCUGAGUGUUUGUGUCCCCACACCACCAAUUCGUAUGUUGAAAUCUAACCUGCAAUGUGAUGGUAUUAGGAGGUGGCCUUUGGCAGGUGAUUAGGUCAUGACAAUGGAGCCCUCAUGAAAAGGAUUCGCACCCUUACAAAACAGGCCCCAUGCAGCUGCCUUGUCCCUUCCACCACAUAAGGACCCAGCAAGAAGGAGCUCUGAAUCAGAAAGGAGCCCUCACCAGACACCAAAUCUGCCUGCUUGAUCUUGGACUUGAUCUUGCACCUCCCCGCCUCCAUAAUGAUGAUAAAUACAUUUCUGUUGCUAAUAAUCUACCCAGUUUAUGGUAUUUGUUAUAGCAGUCCAAACAGAAAAAAAAUUGCUUGUUUUUUCUUCCUUAUUUAGUCUUACUUCAGUGGAAUCUGUUCAUUCCUAUUUUAGGCCAUAUUUAUCCUUAUUCUCAGUGUCUGUAUUUUGGGCGACCUUGAAGGUUUGACAAUCCCCCUUUGGCCUUUUAAAGUAGAGGGCAGAGUGUUGUGCACAGUCUGGACCCAACUGUGUUUUAUCUUGGCCUUUUUGGCUGUGGAUCUGUUGUCCCGUGCAGGGAUUUUUUGGUCUCUUGUUCAGGUCUUUUUAUGAGGGCGGGAAUUGAUUCUGUAAUGAUGUGAAAACAUAAGUAUUUUGCAAGCCAACAAUUUUGCACACUGCAGAGCCUACUGCUCUUCGUUCUUCUAGGCUAAACUUCUCCGAUGAUUGACUUAUGGAUCAAAGCCCCAGACCCAUUGCAUGCUGGAAGAUGAAGCUGGUGGAAAUUAAAGUGGAAUUGGAAUAAGAAAAGACUUACUGAGAGAAAGGGACAGUUCUCAGUGAUUUUAGAAAGCAGGUUAAGGGUGUAGUUUGCUCCCCUUUGUGUCCAAAGCCCAGUUUCUGGGAGGUGGGGCACAUAUUUUGGCUAGGUGAAGGAAAUUCUGCUGUUUGACCAUCCUCCUCAUUCUUUGAUUAAGGUCUCAGGGCUUCAACUGAGUUUUAGUUUUACUAACAUUUAGUUAGUAGAUGUUUCUUCAGUUUUUUCAUAGGUCAUUGAGCCAUUUGUCAAGAUUCCAGGACUGUGAAAACAUCAAUACGAUGAUGAGCCAGUGAGCCUAAGUCACAAGUUGUUUUUUGCCAUCAUAAUUCAAAAAUCUUUUUUUUUUUUUGAGACGGAGUCUCAUUCUGUCGCCCAGGCGGGAGUGCUGUGGCGCGAUCUCCGCUCACUGCAAGCUCCGCCUUCCGGGUUCACGCCAUUCUCCUGCCUCAGCCUCCCGAGUAGCUGGGACUACAGGCGCCCGCCACUGCGCCCGGCUAAUUUUUUGUAUUUUUAGUAGAGACGGGGUUUCACCGUGGUCUCGAUCUCCUGACCUCGUGAUCCGCCCGCCUCGGCCUCCCAAAGUGCUGGGAUUACAGGCGUGAGCCACCGCGCCCGGCCCAAAAAUCUUUUUAAGAGAAGCCCUCCAGCCCUAUCCUAGAUAUCAGGGAGCUACCCUCCCUGGCAAACAACCUCUUGGCUUUUGUGCCAUUUGGGGCUGUAUUAUUUUGUUUGAGUGAGAUGUCAAGUUUACUGACUGAAGAGUUUUUUAUUGGUUAGGUGGAAGUGACACUAGCACAUAAAUAUAUUUUGAGGCUUGUGUGGAUUGGAUAUUACUGAUUGGAUAUUACUGAGGCUCAAGUUAAUGGUGUUUUAGGUUAAAAACUUACCUAGUAUGUGGAGCAUCAGUUUGUUCAGUAUACAAUUCUAUAAGAAGCUUUCUUUGGUCUAGUGAGCCACUGGCCUGAAGACUUCUACAGACUGUUGUUCCGCAAAUCAGAGUUUAAAUGCAGAUGUCUCCUAGACCAACAAAUUGCUGCAAUUUUCUACCAUGUUUUCUUGGUCACUGCUUCAUCCUGCUGAGGAGCCUGAUGGCAGUGGGGUAGUGCCUGGAAGUAUAAUUUUGUUGAAGGGUGUAAGGCAAACACUUAUUACCAUUUGUAAUGCUCUGCUUACUUGCUUAUUAUCUGUCUCCUCAGUAGUCUCUAAGCAGUGGCAUGCAUAUCUGUUUUAUUCUCUACUGUGUGCCCAGGGUCUAGCACAGUAUCUGGUGCUCCAUGUAUAUUUGAUGAAUGAAUGAAUGAACUUGAAAGAGUCUCAGUGCCAAGUACCCACAGGUUACAGGGAAGUUAUAGACAAGUUUUUGCCUUUAUUUGUUAACCUGCAACUUCAAUUAACUUGGUUCCAAAACCUCUUCAGAUGUAGUAGAAUUACUACAUGUAGUGCAUACUGUUGGGUGGAAUUCAAACAAAAUGGUGUUUCUGAAGAAGAGCAAUUGCAUGUGAAAUACAUUUUCUUGUGACUAGCAAAAAUAAUUUAUUAGCCUCUAGCUCAUUUAAAUUUGAUUCCUAGAAAGCAGUUAUAGUAAAACACAAAAGCCUGUGAGAAAAGAUGCGAUAUUUUCCCCUUUGGCCCUACUCGCCCACCCCUUCUGGGGCUUGGGGCACAGUCAUCUCCCCCUGGGGCCUUAUCCAGAUUAGGUAAUGGAAACAUUUUUCCUCGGGUGGGAUGGAGAUUUGGAGACUUUCUGGGUUCUAGGGUUAUACUGAGAGGGACUUUAUUUUGCUAGAGACUUCCUUAAUGCCGGAGACAUUUUGAGGCCAGAUCUGGAAGUUCCUUUCCCUGAUUCACUGAAGAGGAAAGAUUCACCCUCUCACUGCCAUUCUGGCCUCUACCCUUUCCAUGGAAGUAAAAUCUAAUGGAACCAAAUGGUGGAGAUGCUUGGCCAGCCACAGAGAAAGAAUGAGAGGAAGCCUCAGGCUCAGGAAGAGGAGCUUUGUAGGCAGCCAAUCCCAGAGAAGCAGACGGGAUGGCUAGUUCAGCCCGGGAGCACCUGCUUUUUGUGAGGCGUCGAAAUCCCCAGAUGCGGUACACAUUGAGCCCAGAGAACCUCCAGAGCCUUGCCGCCCAGAGCUCCAUGCCAGAGAACAUGACCCUGCAGCGGGCCAACAGCGACACCGACCUGGUGACUUCUGAGAGCCGCUCCAGCUUAACUGCCAGCAUGUACGAGUACACGCUGGGGCAAGCCCAGAACCUCAUUAUCUUCUGGGACAUUAAAGAGGAGGUGGACCCCAGUGAUUGGAUUGGACUUUAUCAUAUAGAUGAGAAUUCUCCAGCCAACUUCUGGGAUUCUAAGAACAGGGGUGUGACUGGAACACAAAAAGGGCAAAUUGUAUGGAGAAUUGAGCCUGGGCCCUAUUUCAUGGAACCGGAGAUAAAAAUCUGUUUUAAAUAUUACCACGGCAUUAGUGGAGCCCUGCGAGCCACGACCCCCUGCAUCACCGUGAAGAACCCAGCUGUGAUGAUGGGGGCAGAAGGCAUGGAGGGAGGUGCUUCAGGAAACCUGCAUUCUCGAAAACUUGUUAGCUUUACAUUGUCAGAUCUUAGGGCAGUUGGGCUAAAGAAAGGGAUGUUCUUCAAUCCUGACCCUUAUCUUAAGAUGUCAAUUCAGCCAGGAAAGAAGAGCAGUUUCCCCACCUGUGCCCACCACGGGCAGGAGAGACGGUCUACUAUCAUCAGUAACACCACCAAUCCAAUUUGGCACCGAGAGAAAUAUUCCUUUUUUGCACUUCUUACUGAUGUCUUAGAAAUUGAAAUUAAAGACAAAUUUGCCAAGAGCCGUCCCAUCAUCAAGCGUUUUCUGGGGAAACUAACCAUUCCAGUCCAGAGGCUGCUGGAGCGACAAGCCAUCGGUGAUCAAAUGCUCAGCUACAACCUUGGCAGAAGGCUCCCAGCUGACCACGUGAGUGGGUACCUCCAGUUUAAAGUGGAGGUUACGUCUUCUGUUCAUGAAGAAAUGCUGUUUUCUCAUUCAGAUGCCUCUCCAGAAGCUGUUGGCACAAUACUUGGAGUCAAUUCUGUGAAUGGAGACUUAGGUAGCCCUUCCGAUGACGAGGACAUGCCAGGGAGCCAUCACGACAGCCAGGUGUGCUCUAAUGGGCCAGUUUCUGAGGACAGUGCUGCCGAUGGAACCCCCAAGCAUUCAUUCAGGACUAGCUCCACUCUGGAAAUAGACACAGAGGAAUUAACCUCUACGUCUUCAAGGACCUCACCUCCCAGAGGACGUCAGGAUUCACUCAAUGAUUACUUAGAUGCUAUCGAACACAAUGGCCACUCCAGGCCGGGGACAGCGACCUGCUCUGAGAGGUCCAUGGGUGCCUCUCCGAAACUGAGGAGUAGUUUUCCCACUGACACAAGACUCAAUGCCAUGCUUCAUAUUGAUUCAGAUGAAGAAGAUCACGAGUUCCAGCAAGACCUGGGUUACCCAUCUUCCUUGGAGGAGGAGGGAGGCCUGAUCAUGUUUAGCAGGGCAUCCAGAGCUGAUGAUGGAAGCCUGACAUCUCAGACAAAGCUGGAGGACAACCCUGUUGAGAAUGAGGAAGCCUCCACACACGAAGCUGCUUCCUUUGAGGAUAAGCCAGAAAAUCUUCCAGAGCUUGCAGAGAGCUCCUUACCUGCAGGCCCAGCCCCAGAGGAAGGUGAAGGCGGCCCAGAGCCUCAACCCAGUGCUGACCAGGGCAGUGCUGAACUGUGUGGCUCUCAAGAGGUAGAUCAGCCCACAAGUGGCGCAGACACAGGGACUUCCGAUGCAUCAGGAGGAAGCCGAAGAGCCGUCAGUGAGACCGAGUCUCUCGAUCAGGGCUCUGAGCCUUCCCAGGUGUCCUCUGAAACAGAACCCAGUGAUCCUGCCAGGACAGAGAGUGUGAGCGAAGCCAGCACCAGGCCUGAGGGAGAGAGUGACCUGGAAUGCGCUGACAGCUCCUGCAAUGAGAGUGUGACCACGCAGCUGUCCUCUGUGGACACACGGUGCUCCUCUCUUGAGAGCGCACGGUUUCCUGAAACCCCAGCCUUUUCUUCUCAGGAGGAGGAAGACGGAGCCUGUGCAGCAGAGCCCACCAGCAGUGGCCCUGCCGAAGGGUCGCAGGAAUCCGUGUGCACUGCUGGUUCUUUACCUGUGGUACAGGUGCCCAGUGGGGAGGAUGAAGGGCCAGGGGCAGAAUCGGCCACUGUACCUGACCAGGAGGAGCUGGGGGAGGUCUGGCAGCGGAGGGGGAGCCUGGAGGGAGCUGCAGCUGCUGCCGAGAGCCCACCGCAAGAAGAAGGCAGUGCUGGGGAGGCCCAAGGCACCUGUGAAGGGGCAACUGCCCAGGAGGAGGGCGCUACUGGAGGUUCUCAAGCCAACGGCCACCAGCCACUGCGAUCACUACCUUCAGUGCGCCAGGAUGUUAGCCGGUACCAGAGGGUGGACGAGGCUCUCCCACCAAACUGGGAGGCACGCAUUGACAGCCACGGCAGGAUCUUCUACGUGGAUCACGUAAACAGAACCACGACGUGGCAGCGACCGACAGCUCCCCCAGCCCCGCAGGUGCUGCAGAGAUCUAACUCCAUACAGCAAAUGGAGCAGCUGAACCGGCGAUAUCAGAGUAUCCGCAGAACCAUGACCAAUGAGAGGCCUGAGGAAAAUACCAAUGCUAUUGAUGGGGCAGGGGAGGAAGCUGACUUUCACCAAGCCAGUGCAGAUUUCCGACGGGAGAACAUCCUGCCUCACUCUACCUCCAGAUCCAGGAUCACGUUGCUGUUACAGUCUCCCCCCGUGAAGUUCCUCAUCAGCCCAGAGUUCUUCACCGUGCUGCAUUCUAACCCUAGUGCCUACCGCAUGUUUACAAACAACACGUGUUUGAAGCACAUGAUCACCAAAGUCCGGAGGGACACCCACCACUUUGAACGCUACCAGCAUAACCGCGACCUUGUGGGAUUCCUCAACAUGUUCGCGAACAAACAGCUAGAGCUGCCGCGGGGAUGGGAAAUGAAACAUGAUCACCAGGGCAAGGCAUUCUUUGUGGACCACAACUCCCGCACCACCACUUUCAUUGAUCCCCGGCUCCCACUUCAGAGCAGUAGACCCACAAGUGCGCUGGUUCAUCGGCAACACCUGACAAGGCAACGCAGCCACAGUGCGGGUGAGGUAGGAGAAGAUUCUCGACAUGCAGGACCACCAGUUCUUCCCAGGCCAUCCAGUACAUUCAAUACAGUCAGUAGGCCACAGUACCAGGACAUGGUUCCAGUGGCUUACAAUGACAAGAUUGUUGCAUUUCUACGUCAACCCAAUAUCUUUGAAAUUCUACAGGAGCGUCAACCUGAUCUUACCAGGAAUCACUCACUCAGGGAGAAGAUCCAAUUUAUCCGAACUGAAGGGACUCCAGGAUUGGUGCGCCUUUCAAGCGAUGCAGACCUUGUUAUGUUGCUGAGCUUAUUUGAAGAAGAGAUAAUGUCGUAUGUGCCUCCACAUGCCUUACUCCACCCCAGCUACUGUCAGUCCCCACGUGGCUCUCCCGUGUCAUCUCCUCAGAACUCGCCAGGUACCCAGCGUGCCAAUGCCCGGGCUCCAGCCCCUUACAAGCGGGAUUUCGAAGCCAAACUGAGGAACUUUUACAGGAAGUUAGAGACUAAAGGAUAUGGACAAGGCCCAGGGAAGUUAAAGUUAAUUAUCCGAAGAGAUCACUUACUAGAAGAUGCUUUUAAUCAGAUUAUGGGCUACUCCAGAAAAGACCUGCAGAGAAAUAAGCUAUAUGUCACCUUCGUUGGGGAGGAAGGGCUGGAUUACAGUGGGCCUUCUAGAGAGUUUUUCUUCCUGGUAUCCAGAGAACUCUUUAACCCAUAUUAUGGCUUAUUUGAAUAUUCAGCCAAUGACACAUACACAGUACAAAUAAGUCCUAUGUCUGCUUUUGUAGACAAUCACCAUGAAUGGUUCCGAUUCAGUGGUAGGAUCCUUGGUCUUGCACUAAUACACCAGUAUUUGUUGGAUGCCUUCUUCACACGGCCCUUUUAUAAGGCUCUUCUCAGAAUUCUAUGUGACCUGAGUGACCUAGAAUACCUUGAUGAAGAGUUCCAUCAGAGCCUGCAGUGGAUGAAAGACAAUGAUAUCCAUGACAUCCUAGACCUCACGUUCACUGUGAACGAAGAAGUAUUUGGGCAGAUAACUGAACGAGAAUUAAAGCCAGGGGGUGCCAAUAUCCCAGUUACAGAGAAGAACAAGAAGGAGUACAUCGAGAGGAUGGUGAAGUGGAGGAUUGAGAGGGGUGUUGUACAGCAAACAGAGAGCUUAGUGCGUGGCUUCUAUGAGGUGGUGGAUGCCAGGCUGGUAUCUGUUUUUGAUGCAAGAGAACUGGAAUUGGUCAUCGCAGGCACAGCUGAAAUAGACCUAAGUGAUUGGAGAAACAACACAGAAUAUAGAGGAGGAUACCAUGACAAUCAUAUUGUAAUUCGGUGGUUCUGGGCUGCAGUGGAAAGAUUCAACAAUGAACAACGACUAAGGUUGUUACAGUUUGUUACAGGCACAUCCAGCAUUCCCUAUGAAGGAUUUGCUUCACUCCGAGGGAGUAACGGCCCAAGAAGAUUCUGUGUGGAGAAAUGGGGGAAAAUCACUGCUCUUCCCAGAGCGCAUACAUGUUUUAACCGUCUGGAUCUGCCUCCCUACCCAUCCUUUUCCAUGCUUUAUGAAAAACUGUUGACAGCAGUUGAAGAAACCAGUACUUUUGGACUUGAGUGACCUGGAAGCUGAAUGCCCAUCUCUGUGGACAGGCAGGUUCAGAAGCUGCCUUCUAGAAGAAUGAUUGAACAUUGGAAGUUUCAAGAGGAUGCUUCCUUUAGGAUAAAGCUAUGUGCUGUUGUUUUCCAGGAACAAGUGCUCUGUCACAUUUGGGGACUGGAGAUGAGUCCUCUUGGAAGGAUUUGGGUGAGCUUGAUGCCCAGGGAACAACCCAACCGUCUUUCAAUCAACAGUUCUUGACUGCCAAACUUUUUCCAUUUGUUAUGUUCCAAGACAAAGAUGAACCCAUACAUGAUCAGCUCCACGGUAAUUUUUAGGGACUCAGGAGAAUCUUGAAACUUACCCUUGAACGUGGUUCAAGCCAAACUGGCAGCAUUUGGCCCAAUCUCCAAAUUAGAGCAAGUUAAAUAAUAUAAUAAAAGUAAAUAUAUUUCCUGAAAGUACAUUCAUUUAAGCCCUAAGUUAUAACAGAAUAUUCAUUUCUUGCUUAUGAGUGCCUGCAUGGUGUGCACCAUAGGUUUCCGCUUUCAUGGGACAUGAGUGAAAAUGAAACCAAGUCAAUAUGAGGUACCUUUACAGAUUUGCAAUAAGAUGGUCUGUGACAAUGUAUAUGCAAGUGGUAUGUGUGUAAUUAUGGCUAAAGACAAACCAUUAUUCAGUGAAUUACUAAUGACAGAUUUUAUGCUUUAUAAUGCAUGAAAACAAUUUUAAAAUAACUAGCAAUUAAUCACAGCAUAUCAGGAAAAAGUACACAGUGAGUUCUGUUUAUUUUUUGUAGGUUCAUUAUGUUUAUGUUCUUUAAGAUGUAUAUAAGAACCUACCUAUCAUGCUGUAUGUAUCACUCAUUCCAUUUUCAUGUUCCAUGCAUACUCGGGCAUCAUGCUAAUAUGUAUCCUUUUAAGCACUCUCAAGGAAACAAAAGGGCCUUUUAUUUUUAUAAAGGUAAAAAAAAUUCCCCAAAUAUUUUGCACUGAAUGUACCAAAGGUGAAGGGACAUUACAAUAUGACUAACAGCAACUCCAUCACUUGAGAAGUAUAAUAGAAAAUAGCUUCUAAAUCAAACUUCCUUCACAGUGCCGUGUCUACCACUACAAGGACUGUGCAUCUAAGUAAUAAUUUUUUAAGAUUCACUAUAUGUGAUAGUAUGAUAUGCAUUUAUUUAAAAUGCAUUAGACUCUCUUCCAUCCAUCAAAUACUUUACAGGAUGGCAUUUAAUACAGAUAUUUCGUAUUUCCCCCACUGCUUUUUAUUUGUACAGCAUCAUUAAACACUAAGCUCAGUUAAGGAGCCAUCAGCAACACUGAAGAGAUCAGUAGUAAGAAUUCCAUUUUCCCUCAUCAGUGAAGACACCACAAAUUGAAACUCAGAACUAUAUUUCUAAGCCUGCAUUUUCACUGAUGCAUAAUUUUCUUAUUAAUAUUAAGAGACAGUUUUUCUAUGGCAUCUCCAAAACUGCAUGACAUCACUAGUCUUACUUCUGCUUAAUUUUAUGAGAAGGUAUUCUUCAUUUUAAUUGCUUUUGGGAUUACUCCACAUCUUUGUUUAUUUCUUGACUAAUCAGAUUUUCAAUAGAGUGAAGUUAAAUUGGGGGUCAUAAAAGCAUUGGAUUGACAUAUGGUUUGCCAGCCUAUGGGUUUACAGGCAUUGCCCAAACAUUUCUUUGAGAUCUAUAUUUAUAAGCAGCCAUGGAAUUCCUAUUAUGGGAUGUUGGCAAUCUUACAUUUUAUAGAGGUCAUAUGCAUAGUUUUCAUAGGUGUUUUGUAAGAACUGAUUGCUCUCCUGUGAGUUAAGCUAUGUUUACUACUGGGACCCUCAAGAGGAAUACCACUUAUGUUACACUCCUGCACUAAAGGCACGUACUGCAGUGUGAAGAAAUGUUCUGAAAAAGGGUUAUAGAAAUCUGGAAAUAAGAAAGGAAGAGCUCUCUGUAUUCUAUAAUUGGAAGAGAAAAAAAGAAAAACUUUUAACUGGAAAUGUUAGUUUGUACUUAUUGAUCAUGAAUACAAGUAUAUAUUUAAUUUUGCAAACUUUUCACUUGUUUGUAUUCUUUUCAUUAUAAGGAAAAGUAGUAUAACACACUUUUUUUUAAGUCACAUAUUUGAUGGUAUACAAGAUGUUUCAGGGCUGGCAUUCUCCAAGCAGCAGAUAAAGGUUGCAUUUCUUUCAAAAAUACAUUCAAAGACCAUGUUAUCCUUCAUUUUGGUUUGAGACAUUUAGUUAUGGUAUUUCAUAUUAUUAGGUAAAAGAUAUUUGAAAUAAAAUGUAUCUCUUUAAUUAUUUCUAACAAAUAUAUUUCUUUAUUAAGGCAUCCAACUUUUUCCCAAAUAACAGUACACUUUAAUGUAUGUAGACAUUCUUAAUUAGUAUAAUCAUCUAGUUGAUACUGUUCUCAGAUUGGGAAUUAUCAAAGAUGUACUUAUCAUAUCAGAACACCAUGCUAACUUAUCUAUUAUUCUUUCUUAGUAAAACAAAACAGCCAGUAAUAACUAUAUAAAAUAUUAAAUAACAUUUCCACAGAAUAAAUUAGACUUUCAUGUACUCUACAAUUAGAAAUAUCCAUAAAUAUUUUCUUCUGGACUGUGAACCCAGAUAACUAGGCUUUCUGGUCUUAUUUUAAGUGAUGCUCUUUAUACUAUAGAAGACACUCUUAAUACAUCAUAUAUGUAUGCAGAACAUCUCUUAGAUGAGAGAACAAGCACAUCAUUGGCAUUCCCUCUGUGCCAGUUUGAUGUUUGUUUGACGAUGGAGCUACAAGAGUCUAAAUCUGCCUUUGAAAAGCUCAGCUCACAGUGUAGUAGAGUAGACUCCAAGGUUCAAAAAAGUGUUUUUAAUAAAAUUUGGUAAGUUCUACAAUCAAGGAAUGAAGAGAGAAGAGAACAGCUUUUUCCAUCUGGGAGAUUCAAUAAUGGCUUCAUAUAUAGAUGAUAGUGUGGCUAAAAAAAAUUACAUCAAUGCUGUUUCUAUUGGGAAGCAAUGGCAAGUAAUAGUAUGUCAAUACUGGUCAAGUGUUGAAGCCAGGAUGCACUUACACAACGAGAGUGUAAAGUGUGUAGGGAGCUGAUCUGUGAAGGAGCAACUCAAAGAUUUUGAAAUUAUCAGUGAAAUGCCAAAACAGGGAAAGUUUCCCUGUUUCCCUUCAUCUAUUCUACAAUGCACCAUUGGUUUUCAGUGUGAAAAAUCCCAAUCCCUGAGCCCAAACCACUUCUGGGGUCAAAACAUUUUUCUUGUGCACAAAAUGAAUGGAUCUUGGUCAAAGAAGUAUGGUCACAAUUUUCUAGCAUAUAUUGCGUUUAUAAUUUAGCAGAAAUUCUGCAAUAAAUAAAGGAAAAUCUGUUUUACCUGUGCAACAAUCAGAAAUGGUAAAAAUGCAUUCAAGUGUUUGAAAGAAAUGGUAGAAUAUGCUUGCAUAGUGCUUUAUAGUUUCAAAGUGCUGUCAGGUACAUCGUCCGUUUAGCUCCUCACGCACUUUGUAGGGUACAAGCAUCAUGUUCCAUCUGGGUUGUGGCUGAUUUUCAUGGAUGGCUUGUGGCAUCAGUUUCAUUACUUCAUAGUCACAAUUCUGUGUUUCAUCUUGAGAAAUGUGGAGACUAAUGUUUGUACCAGUAUAUUCCACAUUCAGUGAGGUUUCCAAGAUGCUUCCUCCAAACUCUCACUUUCUUAAACAGAUACAUUUAAAAUAUGACACCUUCUGAAAAGUCCAUAAAGAAAUUAGUAUAUUCAUGGAAAAAAUUUCCCCGUAGACUUAUUUGCAUUUCAUGACUUGACAUGAGAAAUUUAAAAAACAGAAGGCAAAAUGUGAUUGCUUUUGAUGGAUUUAUACAGAAUAGUCAUUUAAUUUUCUCAAGUAUUAUUUGGAAACAAGAUAAUGGAAAACAUUAAUCAGAAGCCUUAUUUUAUUUUUAAAUUUUUAAUAGGGAUGGAUCUAGUAAGCCCUAAUAGCUGAGUUCCAGUGAUAAAAUUCACAAAUUUUAUUUAUGAUUGGACCACUUCUAACAAGGCAAAUAUCUUAUAAUGAAGAUAGGAGUCUGUUCAAUUUAACCUUAUUCAGGAAACUCCGUAUUUAUGUGAAAUGAUGCAAUGCCAUUAUUAAGAGGUAUCUGUAACCCUGCAUAAUAAAAACAUGCAUAAGAAGAAUGUGGUCUAAUCUCCAAACUGAGUCUCAGUUUCAGGGCCUUUUGCUUUCUUUGUUUGUUUGUUUGAGACAGUCUGGCUCUGUCAUCCAGGCUGGAGUGCAGUGGCACAUGAGCUCACUGCAACCUCCACCUCCCAGGCUCAAGCGAUCCUCCCACCUCAGCCUCCUGAGUAACUGGGACUACAGGCGCAUACCACCACACCUGGCUAAUUUUUGUAUUUUUGUAGAGACAAGGCCCAGGCACGUCUCAAACUCUUGAGCUCAAGCGAUCCGCCCGCCUUGGCCUCCCAAAGUGCUAGGAGUAAUUAUAGGUGUGAGCCACCAUGCUGGCAGUUGUUUUUGUUUAUUUGUGAUAAGGUCUGGCUGUCACCCAUGCUGGAGUGCAGUGGCAUGAUCUUGGCUCACUGCAACCUCUGCCUUCCAGGCUCAAGCCAGCCUCCCACCUCAGCCUCCGAGUAGCUAGGACUACAGGCAUGCACCACCAUGCCCAGCUAAUUUUUUUAUAUUUUUUGUAGACACAGGGUUUUGCCACGUUGCCCAGGCUGGUCUUGAACUCCUGAGCUCAAGCAGUCCUCCCACCUUGGCCUCCCGAAGUGCUGGGAUUACAGACGUGAGCCUCUGGGCCUUGCUCUGUUUUGUCUGCUUUCUGAUUUAGUAGGUGAGGGACAGCACUCUGGACCUUAGCCAUUUUACUUCCAUCUUACUGCCGUGAGUUUGAUGAGAAUGUCACUUUUAGACUCUAAUUUUCAAAAACUUAGUUUCUUUCCCAUUCAUUUGUGUUUUCCAAAUUAAUUUGUUUGUCUAGUAUGGAUGCAAAGGAAUGCUGAAGACAUUAAAGCUUUCUGAAUUGUGGCUUAAGGCCAGCUACUGCCCACUGAAAGGAUGAUAAAAAUAAAAAAGGAGGAAAGAGGAGCCCAGCAGUUGUGCCACCCCGCAAGAAUAUAAUGCUAAUUAUUGACCAACUGUCAAGAUUCAGAGUGGUAACUGCAUUCCGAGGAGCUGUCAGGAAGGAUGACCGUGUGUGUGCUGUCCAUAUCAUAGCCAUCUGGGUCAGAAGGAGCGAAAGGAUGGUUAGGACAGGAGUGUAGUGGAGGGAAAGUUAAAACAACGGUAGAUGGAUCAUCUUAGGGCUUGCUGGUGGGGGUAGGAACAUACUUCAAUUUGGUUUCAGACUGAGAAGAAGAAAGCUAUGCUCCCUGAUGAAGGCACAGUUUGAUCUACUAGAUGGGAAAUACCCUCAUUUUAUAACUUCAGUAAUUUAACAUUUUCUGUAUUGCAAAGUGGAAUUUAGUCCCAAAGUAUUAAAGCUAACCAUAGCUUGAUCAGGAGAUUUGACAAUUUAGCAUAAAAUUAUGUUGUGGAUUUUUUUAUUUAAGAAUUAUUGUUACUAUUAUUGAACACCAUGUAUGAAAUGAAAGAAAGGGUGCUUUUAUUUCAUUAUACUUAUUUGGUUUUUUUAGCGGACAUCCCUUGACAUUAGAAUAGCAUUUGAGACAUUUUCAUGAUUUCUAAAGAUAACUUAAAUGCUCUCUGUUAAUCUGGAAAGUGAAAUCCUAAGAGUGAGGUUGCAAAUGGAGACUAAAUUAGUGUUUCCAAGUCAGGAAGUUAAUCAAGACCGGAAAUAGAUUUGCUUAGAUUUUAUCUGCAGAGUCGUUUAUUUGGCUUUCGUAAUUGAACAGCUCAGCAGAAUAAGAUGGCCCUAGUUGUAUGGUUUCUGGGGAACACAGGAGAAUUAAAUUUAUAUAUGUGAUUUUUAUGUGUAGUGCCCUUGGGCAGGUGAUAUCUUUCUAUAUGACUUUUAAGAUAUUACAACCUGAGGAGUGUGGAUAGCCGUGUUGUGUGAUUCAAACUGAAUCAGCUAUUACUGAUGCAGGUAAGGAACCAUCAGUCAACUUCUGGUUACUAUCACCUUCAUAAAAAAGAAUGGAUGAUGUUCAGGAAUUACCUUGGAAGGAUUAACCAGGAAUUAACACAGAAUGGGAUGUUCUUUUAGGACCCUAAUGCUCUAAAAGAUAAAAUUACAACCUAUUUUUCUUUAUAUGAUAGCAUAAGUAAAAUUUGGGGCUGUUAAUAUGUUGGAAAGUGCUUAAAAUUACAUGUUUUUAUAAUAGGGAUGCAGGCAUUCCAAAAUAAAUGAAUAAAAAUACAUGCAUCUCUCUCGCCUCUUACUGAAAGUAUUAAUCUAAUUUUAUAGUAAUGAUUACUUUUUAAUAUUAAGGCUCUGUAAAAAAAUUAUUUCUAAGAUUUCAGUAGAACACAGGUGGUGUAUUUUUUUAAGCUUUUAAUUUCUCUUCACCAACCUCAGUCAUUACGUUCACCACACAGUGUGUCACAGUUAAUAGUGGUAUUUCAGUUUUUGCGUUGAUUUAAGCUUCAUAUUUAUUUAAUGUGACUUUUGAUGGAGAAUAAUAAUGGGAGAUGCUUGCUGUUAGCAUUAAGGUUAUACAGCUCUCACUUCACCUUAUAUGUAAUUUUUUUUUCAAAGUAAAUAAUGCAGAUUGUUGACAUCCUAGAAAUGGUUUCUGGGUGGUAUUAUAUGGGGCCUAGGACUCUGAACUGGGACUAGUUGUUUAUUUUCUGGGAAGUCUGUAUUCUUAUUCUCAACUGAACCCCUGACUCUUUUGUUGUAUUUUUUAUGAUUCCGAAAUGCUUUGAGGGAAAGAUAUUUUAAUGUGUACAAUUUGUUUUAUUUUCAUACUGAUCUCUAUUUUUGUUUAAAACCAUGUUGCAUCAUGAAAUCACUUAAUCCAAAAUAAAUCUUCUUUAAAAAAAAUAGAUUAUGACUUUUCUGUAAUACUUUUGGGGAGGGAAAACUCAGAAGGGAGGAGAAUAGAAGUAGAGAUAAAGAUUUCAUGGCAUUAGUUUGCAGCUCUAUAAAUAUUGGAGGUUCUGUUUUCAUAGUAUUUAUAGUAUUUUGUUUAUUUUUAUUUAUAUUUUUAUUAUUUAUUAAUAAAAUAUUUGUUUAUUUUGUUUGGAAUCUACUUUGUUUAUCCCUACAAGAAUAUUUUACUGUUUGAUGGGCUGUUAAUGUUAAAGGAAUGAAUUAUAAUACAAAUCAUAAUUUCUUAACUCA